GUCUCUCGCCGCAGCCUGAGCUCCAGGUCUCCCCUUCGCUGCUCUGUGUCCUCUGCUCCUAGAGGCCCAACAUCUGUGGCCCUGUGACCUGCAGGUAUUGGGAGACCCACAGCUAAGACACCGGGACCCCCUGAAAGCCUAGAAAUGGACGACUUGAAAUAUGGAGUGUAUCCUCUCAAGGAAGCAAGUGGAUGCCCUGGGGCUGAGAGGAAUCUUCUAGUUUACUCUUAUUUUGAAAAGGAGACAUUGACAUUUAGGGAUGUGGCCAUAGAAUUCUCUCUGGAGGAGUGGGAAUGCCUGAACCCUGCUCAGCAGAAUUUAUAUAUGAAUGUGAUGUUAGAAAACUACAAAAACCUGGUCUUCUUGGGUGUUGCUGUCUCUAAGCAAGACCCAGUCACCUGUCUGGAGCAAGAAAAAGAGCCCUGGAAUAUGAAGAGACAUGAGAUGGUGGAUGAACCCCCAGGAAAAACUGAUCAUGAUCUGCGGCUCAGAGAGCUGGAACUGAGUCAAUAAACUGCUUCAGGGACCACAGUAAAAACCAAGCUAUGUGUUCUUAUUUUACCAAAGACCUUUGGCCAGAGCAAGACAUAAAAGAUUCUUUUCAACAAGUAAUACUGAGAAGAUAUGGCAAAUGUGAACAUGAGAAUUUACAGUUAAGAAAAGGCUCCGCAAGUGUAGAUGAGUAUAAGGUGCACAAAGAAGGUUAUAAUGAGCUAAACCAGUGUUUGACAACUACCCAGAGCAAAAUAUUUCCAUGUGAUAAAUAUGUGAAAGUCUUUCAUAAAUUUUUAAAUGCAAAUAGACAUAAGACAAGACAUACUGGAAAGAAACCUUUCAAAUGUAAAAAAUGUGGCAAAUCAUUUUGCAUGCUUUUACACCUAAGUCAACAUAAAAGAAUUCAUAUUAGAGAGAAUUCUUACCAAUGUGAAGAAUGUGGCAAAGCUUUUAAAUGGUUCUCAACCCUUACUAGACACAAGAGAAUUCAUACUGGAGAGAAACCCUUCAAAUGUGAAGAAUGUGGCAAAGCUUUUAAGCAGUCCUCAACCCUUACUACACAUAAGAUAAUUCAUACUGGGGAGAAACCAUAUAGAUGUGAAGAAUGUGGCAAAGCCUUCAACCGGUCCUCACACCUUACUACACAUAAGAUAAUUCAUACUGGAGAGAAGCCCUACAAAUGUGAAGAAUGUGGCAAAGCUUUUAACCAGUCUUCAACCCUUAGUACACAUAAGUUCAUUCAUGCUGGAGAGAAACCCUACAAAUGUGAGGAAUGUGACAAAGCUUUUAAUCGAUUCUCAUACCUUACUAAACAUAAGAUAAUUCAUACUGGAGAAAAAUCUUACAAAUGUGAAGAAUGUGGCAAAGGCUUUAAUUGGUCCUCAACCCUUACUAAACAUAAAAGAAUUCAUACUGGAGAGAAACCCUACAAAUGUGAAGUGUGUGGCAAAGCCUUUAAUGAGUCCUCAAACCUUACUACACAUAAGAUGAUUCAUACUGGAGAGAAACCCUACAAAUGUGAAGAAUGUGGCAAAGCUUUUAACCGGUCCCCACAACUUACUGCACAUAAGAUAAUUCAUACUGGAGAGAAACCUUACAAAUGUGAAGAAUGUGGCAAAGCUUUUAGCCAGUCAUCAAUCCUUACUACACAUAAGAGAAUUCACACUGGAGAGAAACCCUACAAAUGUGAAGAAUGUGGCAAAGCUUUUAACCGAUCCUCAAAUCUUACUAAACAUAAGAUAAUUCAUACAGGAGAGAAAUCUUACAAAUGUGAAGAAUGUGGUAAAGCCUUUAACCAAUCCUCAACUCUUACUAAACAUAGGAAAAUUCAUACUAGACAGAAACCCUACAACUGUGAAGAAUGUGACAAUACAUUUAACCAGUCCUCAAACCUUAUUAAACAAAAUAAUUCAUACUGGAGAGAAACUCUACAAAUGUCAAGAAUGUGGGAAAGCCUUUAAGCAGUCCUCAACUCUUACUAAGCAUUAAAUAUUGGCCGGGUGCGGUGGCUUAUGCAAAAUGGCUCCCAGCAUUUUGGGAGGCUGAGGUGGGUGGAUCACAAGGUCAAGAGAUCGAGACCAUCCUGGCCAACAUGGUGAAACCCUGUCUCUACUAAAAAUACAAAAAUUAUCUGGGUGUGGUGGCACGUGCCUGUAUUCCCAUCUACUCGGGAGGCUUAGGCAGGAUAAUCACUUGAACCUGGGAGGUGGAAGUUGCAGUGAGCCAAGAUUGUACCACUGCACUCCAGUUUGGCAACAGAGUGAGACUCCGUCUCAAAAAAAAUUUAUACUGUACAAAAACCCCACAAGUGUGAAAAACAUGGCAAAGCCUUUAAGAAGCCCUCAAUUCUUAACAGACAUAAGAUAAUUUAUACUGGAGAGAAACUCUACAAAUCAGAAAGAUGUGACUACUUUUGACAACGCCUCAAACUUUUCUAACCAUAAAAGUAAUUAUACUGGUGAGAAAUCCUAGAAAUCUGAAGAGUGAGAUAAAGCCUUUAAAUGGUUGUCACACUUCAUUGUAGGUAAGAUAAUUCAUACUGGAGAAAACGCCUACAUGUGUGAACAAUAUGGCAAAACUUAAUGCUCACACUUUAUUGCUAGGAAAGCAUUUAUACUUGAGAUAAAUUAUACAAAUAUAAAGACUGUGAAAAAGCCAUCAUUAUCUGCUCACAUUUUACUCAACACAGAGAGUUCCUGCUUAAUAAAAGCAUUAUAAGUGCAAUUACUGUCAAAAGAUCUUUCAGAAAAUAUAAGCUUUUUUAGUGAAGAGUAUUUAUUUUGAAGUUGAACAUCACAAAUAUAAAAAGGGUUGUAGUGCCUUUACUUGUAUCACAGAUCUUUUUGUAGACAUUUUCUUCUAGAGGAAAACUCUGAAGCAGUUGAUCAAACUUUGUUCAACAUCAGGGAAUUUAUAUUGAAAAAUUGUGCAAAUAUAAUAAAUUUGGAAAAACAAUUUUUCAAAAACUACAGCUUAGAAAUCAACAGUUAUACUAGAAUAUAUUUUUUCCAGAUGCAGUAAAAGUAAAAUAUUUAAUCCAUAAUUAAGUCUAUGCAAAUAUCAGAGAAUUUAUGGUAGAAAUAUAUAAGGUACUGACACUUCAGAUAUACUAAAUCAGAGUGCUAAGUAUAGAAAAUCUGAAACUAAAGUUGGUAGAAAAGUUAUUUGUAUAGAACUUUAAGAGGAUCAGAAGGUUUUUUGCAGAGUUAUAAUUACAUUCAAAGUAUACUUUAUUUCUUGAAAAAUAUUACAGAUUUUUUGAAAAUUGAAUAAUGUCAUCAUUCAACUCUGAAAUUAUUUCCUGUUGUUUCUUCAUUCCUAUUGGAUUCACAUGUGAAAGCAUGGGGUUAAUUGUUGCUACAUCAAAGAGAGAGAUUCUUUUGUUUGUUUGUUCGUUUGUUUUUUGAGACUGAGUUUCACUCUUUCGCCCAGGCUGGAGUGCAUUGGCAUGAUCUCAGCUCACUACAACCUCUGCCUUCUGGUUUCAAGCAACUCUUCUGCCUCAGCAUCCCAAGUAGCUGGGAUAACAGGUGCCAGCCACCAUGCCCAGCUAAUUUGUGUAUUUCUAGUAGAGAUGGGGUUUCACCAUAUUGGCCAAGCUGGUCUUGAACUCCUGACCUCAUGUGAUCCGCCCGCCUCAGCCUCCCAAAGUGCUGGGAUUACAGGCUUGAGCCACCACGCCCAGCCUGUAGCAUAUUUUAAUAGGAGAAUACAAUAUAUAAUAGUAGCAGGGUUAAGUAAGGCAUCCAUCAUCUGUAGCAUUUCUCCUUUGUUUUACAAACAAUCCAAUUCUACACUUUAAAAAAAAAUUUUUAAAUGUACAAUUAAAUUUUUAUUUACCACAGUGUUAUUUUUAUCGUCAUAAUAAAAAUUAUAUACGAGUAUAAAUGAAAUUCAUUUCUAAAUUCUUAAUAAAUAUUUUCUCAUGCCAGGUGUGGUGGCUCACGUCUGUAAUCCCAGCACUUUGACAGGCUGAGCGAGGGAGUGGAUCUUGAGGUCAGCAGUUCGAGACCAGCAUGGCCAAUAUGGAGAAAUCCCGUCUCUACUAAAAAUACAAAAAUUAGCCAGGCGUGGUGGCAUGUGCCUGUAAUCCCAGCUACUCAGGAGGCUGAGGCAGGAGAAUCGCUUGAACCUGGGAGGUGGAGGUUGCAAUGAGCCAAGAUCACCCCACUGCACUCCAGCCUGGGCAACAGAGCGAGACUCCAUCUCAAAAAGUAAAAUAUAUUUUCAAAUUUUCUAUAUAUUUUUCUUUGAACAUGUGGCCUGUCUGCCUGCAAACAUAUACAGACUUUUAGUUUUGAUUCAUAUAGAGUUAAAUACAUGUUAGUCUAAAGACAAAUCUUAGGUGUAAGAAAAUUAUGGAGUUAAGUAUGUGUGUGUGAGUAUGAGUUUGUACAUAUUUUCAGAAGGAAAGAAUGAUACGGGAACAAAAAUCAUUUUAAUAUGGUGACUACUAUAAAACUAAAAACCUAAAAAAUGCUGAAAGCAAAUGUAUACUUUUUGGUUUGUAUUGAAUUUAUUACUGUACAGUCUAUGACUUAGAGUUCUGAAUCUUCCCAAGCAAAUUCUCUGUAUAUACUUGCCUGGUACUCAUGCUAGACCCAUACUUUUUUUGUUUCUUACAUUUUUUUUGUUUUAUAUUUUAUGAAGUAUUCAUUAUGUGAGCUGGUCUGCGAUUAUAAGAAUUUUUAUGAAAUUUAGUGCACACAAAAUAAUCUUUAGAUGUAAUUCCAAAAGUAGUGUAUUAAGUUACAUUUUAUUUAGUUAGAGCACUCCAUUUUGUUCUUUUAAGAGGAGAACAAUAUAUAGGUUUUCUUUAGUGAUUUGUUCCUUUCACUUUUUAUAAUUGACAUAAGCAUAUUUAUUGAGUCAAUUUGUUCAGCUAAGUACUAGGGAGGCUUCAUUAGUCAUGAGGAUGUUUUUAUAUAUAAAUGUAGCAAACAUAUAUUACAGUUUUCACUGUGUAAUAGAUUAUCCAUAAUAAUUCAUAAAUAUUCCUGCUGAAGUUAGUUUGUAACUUCAAGUCAAAGAUGAAAAAUAUCAAUGGUGAAGAUUGAUUGUUCAUAUAGAGAGGACAUUUUUUUUCCAGACUGUAAAACUGAAUCUUGUUGAAUUUAAAGAGAAAUUCUGGCAGAGGCAGAUGAAUCACCUGAGGUCAGGAGUUUGAGACCAGCCUGAUGAAUAUGGUGAAACCCAGUCUCUACUAAAACUACAAAAAUAGCCAGGCAUGGUGGUGGGUGCCUGUAAUCCCACUCGGGAGGCUGAGUCAGGAGAAUUGCUUGAACCCGGAGGUGAAGAUUGGAGUAAGCCAAGAUUGUGCCGUUGCACUACAGCCUGGGCGACAGAGCGAGACUCCAUAUAAAAAAAAAAAAAAAAAAAAAAGAGCUGGGCGUGGUGGCUCACGCCUGUAAUCCCAGCACUUUGGGAGGCCAAGGUGGGCGAAUCACUUGAGGUCGGGAGUUUGAGACCAGGUGACCAACAUGGAGAAACUCCAUCUCUACUAAAAAAUACAAAAUUAGCCCGGUGUGGUGGCGCAUGCCUGUAAUCCCAGCUACUCGGGAGACUGAGGCAGGAGAAUCGCUUGAACACGACAGGUGGAGGUUGCAGUGUGGCGAGAUUGCACCAUUGCACUCCAGUCUGGGCGACAAGAGGGAAACUCCAUCUGAAAAAAAAGAGAAAUUCUUUUAUUUUCUACUUCUCUUCAGAUUUGUCUUAUGCAUUUUCCAACUAUGUAUGCAUCACAGCUAUUCUUUUUCUGAGUUAUAGCUACAGUUUUCUUACUGUUGUCUUCAUGCCAUUUCAUUUCACAUGGUACUUUGUAGAUUUUGAUGAGGAAGUUGGUAUUUUUAGUGCACACAAAAAUUGGUUUUAACUGUAGAGUUUGCUUAUCAGAACAGUUAAAAGGCAGCCAGGUGUGGCUCACGCCUGUAAUCCCAGCACUGAGAUAGGCCAAGGAGGGUGGAUCACUUGAGGUCAGGAGUUUGAGACCAGCCUGACCAACAUGGUGAAACCCUGUGUCUACUAAAAAUACAAAUUUAGCCACGCGUGGUGACGCACGCCUGUAAUCCCAGCUACUCGGAAGGCCGAGGGAGCAGAAUCGCUUGAACCUGGGAGGUAGAGGUUGCGGUGAGCCGAGACUGGGCCACUGCACUUCAGCCUGGGCAACAAGAGCGAAAUUCUGUCUAAAAAAAAAAAAAAAAGAUAAAAGGUGCAAUACUGUCCACAGGUAAGAUAAUUAAAUUAGUCAGCUUUGUUUUUAAAAGAAAAAUCUUACUAGAUUCUUAUACAAAGUGUGGCAAAUAUAAAACUUGCUUGAAAAUACAGAAAUUAAAUUUUUAAGAGAGUUAAUGGUAAGUAAACAAUUUUAAAGUUAAUUUUCUAUGAUAUACUUACAGCACAACUUAUAUUUCCAUGCAGAAUCUUUUAUUUUUAAGUGUGAGUGUUAAAGGUUACAAAAUAAUGAAAUGACUUCAGUGGAUUUAAAAUUUUGAAAAAUAAUGUCUUUUCUAUAUUGAUUUUACAAUUUGGAGAAAUUUUUCACUCAUUUUUUAUAUAUUUUUUAGUGGGAGAGGUUUAGUCUACAGUUUUUAUUUUUAGUCACCAAACUGUAGCCAACUCUUGGGUCAUUUUCUCUGAAAAACAUUUGGAGAUCAUGACAGCGUUUGGAUUAAAACAUUUCUGUUACUUUGCAUGCAAACUAGUUUACUGUGUUCACAGAGUGGCCAGUCAUGGGACCAUAAGCAACACCUGCUCUUUGAGUGUCUUUCAUACCGUUACCAUCAGCACCAGAAACUCCAGGUGCCCCAAGCUUAAAGUAAAAAUCCUAAAGUACGUUGGCUCCUCCCAUGCAAUGUGCUGGGUCCAAACCAUGCUGUUAAAUAUCAGAAGUUUCUAUGGUUAUGAUUAAAAAAUUAAAUGACAAUAAUAGCCCCAAAACUAUAUAUUUUUGAUACUAUUUAACCAAGAUUAUCACAAAGACACAGUAUUUGACACAUUGUUAUUCUUCUAUGUUUUAUAAAUAUUUUAAUGUGACAGGUAGAAUCUGUACUUUUUCUGUAGAACGUAAUAUUUUGAAGUAUAUAUAUAGUUAAAUUAUUAUUUCUAGGUAAUUAAUAAUUUAUCUCACAUUGGUCAGACAUGAUGGCUCAUGCUUGUAAUCCCAGCAAUUUGGGAGGCCGAGGCAGGCAGAUCACAUGAGGUCAGGAGUUCGGGACCAGCCUGGCGACCAUGGGGAAACCCUGUCUCUACUAAAAAUACAAAAUAAGCAGCGUGUGGUGACACAUGCCUGUAAUCCAGCUACCCUGGAGGCUAAGGCAGGAAAAUGGCUCAAAUCUGGGAGGUGGUUGUUGCAGGGAGCCGAGAUUGCACCACUGCACUCCAGACUGGGGGACAGAGUGACUAUCAAAAAAAAAAAAAACUUUACCUCAUAUGGUGAACAUUUUUGUUUUGAGACCACAUGACACUGUCAUCAUUUUUCAAAAAUCCAAAUACAUUAUUAUGAACUAUAGUCACCAUGUUGUGCAAUAAAUCUCUUGAACUUAUUUCUUCCAUUUGACUAUAAUUAUGUAUUAUUUCACAAACAUGUUUCCAGCCUUCCAUUUCUUAUAAAUAACUUGCAUCUGAUGGUCACCAUUUUACUCUCUACAUCAAUGGGAUUAAGUUUUUUGGAAUCCAUGUGUAAGUGAAAUUAUGAGACACUAAUCUUUCUGUGCCUUGCUUAUCCCAACUAAUACAAUGUCCUCCAACUUCAUCCAUGUGAUUGAGAAUAAUAGUUUUUGUUUUUUUUUUAAGGCCAGGAGUGGUGGCUCACACCUGUAAUCCCAGCUCUGGGAGGCCAAGGCCAGUGGAUUGCUUGAGCCCAGGAGUUUGAGACCAGCCUGGACAACGUGGAAAAACCCCAUCUCUACUAAAAAUACAAAAACAACAAAACAAAAACAAAAAACACCUCAGCUGGGUGUGGUGGUGCAGGCCUGUAAUCUCAGCUACUCCAGAGGCUGAGGCAUGAGAAUCCCUUGAACCACAGAUGCAGAGGUUGCAGUGAACUGAGAUCAUGCCACUGCACUCCAUCCUGGGCAACAGAGUGAGACUCGGUCUCAAGAGGGAAAAUAAGGCAUUUUUCUCAUUUAAAUAAUAAAUAGUAUUCCAUUAUGUAUAUCAACCACAUUGUCUUUAUUUACUCAUUAGAUGUUGAACUGUUUAUUCUGUAUUUUGGCUAUUGUGAAACAAGUGCUGCAAACAGAAGUGCAAAUGUUUCUUUAUUCUUAUUUUGUUUUGGAUAUAUACCCAGUAGUGCGAUUGCUGUAUUACCUGGUAGUUUUUUUGAUAAAUCUGUAUUUUGUUUUUCGUAAUGGCUAUCCUCAUUUACGUUCACACCAACAGUGUGCAAGGAUUCCGUUUUCUUCACAUCUUUACCAACACUUUUUUCUUUUUCUUUUAAUAAGAGUUAUUCUAACAGGAAUGAGUUGAUAUAGGGAUUUUUUUUUUGGCUUGUCUUUUUGUGAUAAUAGUCAACAUUGAGCAUUUAAAAAUAUAUCCGUUGGACAUAUGUAUGACUUUUCUUGAAAAAUAUUUAUUUCAGCUAUUUCCUUUUUUUUUUUUUUCUUUUUGAGAUGGAGUUUUGUUCUUGUUGCCCAGGCUGGAGUGCAAUGGCACAAUCUCGGCUCACUGCAACCCUUGCCUCCCGGAUCAAGUGAUUGUCCUGCCUCAGCCUCUCAAGUAGCUGGGAUUACAGGCAAAUGCCACUGCGCCCAGCUAAUUUUGUAUUUUUAGUAGAGACGGGGUUUUUCUAUAUUGGUCAGGCUGGUCUCGAACUUCUGACCUCUGGUGCCCACCUCAGCCUCCCAAAGUGCUGAGAUUACAGGCAUGAGCCACCGCGUCCGGCCUAUUAUUUUUAAUAAUUUUUUAUUGUUGUCAUUUUAAAUACACUUUUGAUAUUAACCUCUUGUCACAUGUAUAAUUUGCAAAUUUUUUCUCCCAUGUUCUAGUUGUCACAUUCUGUUGAUUGUAUCAGAUUUUGUCCAGCAGCUUUUUAAUUUGAAGUGAUCUGACUUAUUUUUCCUUUUGUGUCCUGGGAUGUUUAGGUUAAAUCAAAAAACUUGCGGCCAGGCGCAGUGGCUCACACCUGUAAUCCCAGCACUUUGGGAGGCCGAGGCAGGUGGAUCACGAGGUCAGAAGUUCGAGACCAGCCUGACCAACAUGGUGAAAUCCUGUCUCUACUAAAAAUACAAAUAUUAGCCGGGCGUGGUUGCACGUGUCUAUAAUCUCAGCUACUCAGGAGGCUGAGGCAGGGGAACGGCUUAAACCCAGAGGCGGAGGUUGUAGUGAGCCAAGGUCAUGCCACUGCACUCCAGCCUUGGCAACAGAAUGAAACUCUGUCUCAAAAAAAAAAAAAAAUUUGCUGCCCAGAACAAUGUUAUAGGGCUUUUGCUCUAUAUUUUGGCAGUAGUAGUUUCAGAGUGUCAGGCCUUACAUUUAAGUACUAAUUUAUUUCGAGUUUAUUUUUACAUAUGGUGUGAGAUGAGGGUCUCAAUUUUUAUCUCUGCAUGUGGAUAUAAAGUUUUCUUAAUUGAAGAUUCUGUUCUUUCCCUUUAAAGUCACCUGUAUUUAAAAUCAACUGUAAAUACAUGGAUAUAUUUCUGCUGUUUUUUUCUUCUGCUCCAUUGACCUAUGUCUCUGUUUUUAUUCAAGUACCAUACUGUUGGUUACCAUAGCUAUGUAGUGUAUUUCAAAGUUAGUCACUUCUUUUGUCUUGAUUGCUUUGGCUAUUCAGGGUCUUUUGUGAUACCAUAUGAAUUUUAGAUAUACUUUUAAAACUUUUCUAUGAAGUAUAUCACGUAUUUCGAUAGAGGUUGCAUUAUACCUGUAGGUCAUUUUGUGUAAUACAAAUAUUAAUGUCAGUUCAUGAAUAGUCCAUUUAUGUAUUAAUUUCUAUUUAGAAUGUAAGGCGUUUCAACUUUUUGGUUAAAUUUAUUUCAAACUAUAGUUAUUGUAGAUGUAAUUGUUUUUGAAUUUCAUUUUGGGAUAGUUAUUAAUGUAGAGAAAUGCUGUGACUUUUUGAUGGUGCUUUUGUAUUUUGAAAGUUUAAUAAAUUUUGUUUAUUUAUUUAUUUAUUUUGAGAUGGAGUCUCGGUCUGUCACGCAGGCUCGAGUGCAGUGGCACGAUCUUGGCUCACUGCAACCUCUGCCUCCCUGGCUGAAGCGGUUCUCCUGCCUCAGCUUCCUAAGUAGCUGAAACUACAGGCGCCUCCUACUACACCCAGCUAAUUUUUUUAUUUCUAUAGAGAUGGGGUUUCCCUACGUUGGCCAGACUGGUCUUGAACUCCUGACCUUGUGAUCCGCCCACCUCGGCCUCCCAAAGUGCUGGAAUUACAGGCAGGAGUCACUGCACCUUGCCUGUUUAUAAUUUUUAAGAUUUACUAAGGUCUUAGGCUUUUUUAUACUUCAGAUUAUGUAUAGGGAUAAAAGAAAAUUAUACAGGAAUAAUUCCUUUUCCUCAAUUUGGAUGCCUUUGAUUUUUUUCUCUAAUUUCUUUGUCUUGGAUAUUUAGUACCAUGUUUAGUAAGUCUGACUAGAGUGGGCAUCCUUGCCUUGUUCUAGCUCUUAGAGUAAAAGCUUACAACAUAUCCCUGUUUAGUAUGUUGUUAGCAGUUUUUUUGGUUAUAUAUGGCAUUUAUUGGCUGAAGUGCAUUUGUUCUAUACCUAAUUUUUUCAGCGAUUUAUCAUAAGGGAAUGUCAAAUUCUGUCAAACUUCUAUUGUGCAUCCAUUUUUUUCUCUUUGCACUCUGCAUAUAUUUAAGUUUUAGAGAUGUGAAAUCACAACUAAUUCUGCAUACAUACAAAAAAAGUCAGAGACUACUAUGAACAUCUCUAUGCCUGCAAAAUAGAAAAUUUGGAGAAAAUAAAUAAACUCCUGGAAACAUACAACUUUCCAGGAUUAAACCAGGAAGGAACAGAACUCUUGAACAGGGCAAAAAUGUAUAAAAUAUAUAAUGAAAUUGAAUUAAUAAUUUAAAAAACCUACCAACUAUAAGGAGCCCUGGAUUAUAUAAAAUCACAGCCGAAUUUUAACACAUAUACAGAGAUGAGCUGGUAUUACUUCUACUGAAUGUAUUACUGAAUGUAUUCCAAAAAAUCCAGGUGGAGUUCCACCCUAACUCAUUAUAUAAAAUCUGUAUCGCUGCACGAGGUGGCUCACGCCUGUAAUCCCAGCACUUUGGAAGGCCGAGGUGGGCGGGUCACCUGAGGUCGGGAGUUUGAGACCAGCCUGCCCAACGUGGUGAAACCCCAUCUCUGCUAAAAUACAAAAUUAGCCAGGCGUGGUGGCAUAUGUCUGUAAUCCCAGCUACUCGGGAGGCUGAGGCAGGAAAAUCGCUUGAACCCGGGAGGUGGAGGUUGCAGUGAGCCGAGAUCGCGCCAUUGCACUCCAGCCUAGGCAAUGAGUGAAACUCCAUCUCAAAAUAAAUUAAUUAAUAAAAUAAAAACCUGUGUCAUCUUGAUACCGAAGUCUAGUGAAGACAACAACAACAAAACUAUAGGCCAAUAUUUUGGGUGAACAUUGAAACAAAAAUCCUCCAUGAAAUAAUAGCAAGCUGAGUUCACAGGCAAAUCAAAAAGUUAUUUUGCCACACUUGUGAACUUUAUAUCACAUGUGCAAGGAUGUUUCAUCAUAUACAAGUCAAUAAGUGUGUUUCACCAUACAAUUAAAAGCAAAAAUUUAUAUGAUUAACACAAUAGAUGCAGAAAAAGCAUUCAAGAAAAUCCAGUAUUCAUUUAUGAAAAUAUUCUCUAAGCAAUGAUGAAACAUACCUCACAAUAAUAAGAGCCAUCUAUGACAAAUCCUCAGCUAACAUACUGAACAGACAAAAGGGGCAUGCAUUUCUCAUUAGAAAAAAAAUAAGACUAUCUAAACAAUUCUAUUUAACAUAGUUCUGGAAGUGCUGGAUAAAUCUAACAAAAUGAAAAAAUAAAUGGCAUCCAAAUAGGAAAAGAAGAAGUGAAAUUACCUUCACUCAUGAUAUAAUUCUCUACCUAGAAAACUUUAAGGAUUUUACCAAAAGACUCCUAAGGUUAAAAAUGACUUCAGCAAAGUCUCAGGAUACAAAAUUGAUAUACAAAAAUGAAUAGCAUUGCCUUACACCAAUAACAUUCAAGCUGAGAACAAAAUCAAGAACAGUUUUCUUUACAAUAGCCAUAAACAAAAAAUAAUAUACUUAGAAAUACAUCAAACCAGGGAGGUAAAAUAUCUCUACAAGAACUAGAAAACAUUACUGAAAGUAAUCAGAGACAAUUCAAAUAAAAAAGCUUUCUAUGCUCAUGGAUUUGAAGAAUGAAUAGAAAAUGUCUAUGCUGCCUAGAGCAGCCUACAAAAUAAGUUUUUGUUUUUUUAUCAAAAUGUCGAUUACUUUUUUUUUUUUUUUGAGACAGUGUUGCUCUGUGGCCUAGGCUGGAGUGCAGUGGUGCGAUCUUGGCUCACUGUAACCUCCACCUCCUGGGUUCAAGUGAGUCUCCUACCUCAGCCUCCCAAGUAGCUGGGAUUACAGGUGCCCACCAGCACACCUGGCUAAUUUUUAUGUUUUUAGUAGAGAUCGAGUUUUGCUGUGUUGGCCAGGCUGGUCUCAAACUCCCGGCGUCCCAAAGUGCUGGGAUUACAGGUGCGACCCACCAUGCCUGGCCCAACCCCAUAUUAUUUCUGGUAACAAAGCACAGAAACAUGAUUUCUCGAAUUUUGCUAGGAUUUUAAUUUACAAAAGAAAGGUGAAUGCCAUUAAAAGGUGUUUAAUACACUCCCACCAGAAACAAGAGGCAAGGCAGGCCCUGGGGGCCUCACAAAGGCGGUCUUAUGCAAGGGUGAGAAAGCAGAGUUAUCAGGGAGGUGGGACUAUUGCUUUAUGAACGUGAUGAUUGGAAGCAAAAACGUGGGGCUUUUUCCUAUUGAAUACAAAGUAAAAUAAUGAAUGCUGGUGUCAGUGGUUGGGAAUAACAACAUUUGCAGGCUCAUGAGAGCUGCCUGACAAAAAGCGUGUAAACAACAGUGAUUGCUCCUGUGGCCCUGUGAUUCAGCAGGUUUAUGGAGCAGUUAAGAAUCGCAGAUGUCAAAUGGCCAACACAGAAUCUAACGACAUGCUUAAUACAAAUUAUUAUUAGUAGAAAUGCUGAAUUGCUUCAUUUCUGCAAUUUCUGCUGCUUCUUAAGAUGCUUUUAAUGAAUAAAAUCUGCCUUAAAAUUUGAUACCUGGUAACUUCUCUCUGUGAGUUUUGAAUUGGCUGAUGUAACCAAAAUGCCAGCUCUUGCCAUCUAACUACCAUUAAAAGGAACUUCUAAAGCUCCGAAGUGGUCAACAGUUUCACUUCCAACUUUUUUAAAAGAUACACAAUUUUCUAAAAAAUUUUUCUUUAUGGGCGAUUGAAUAGUUGGGCUUUGGCUAAUUCCUCAUUAGCAAUAGAAUUAUGUAUAUUUUGCAAACUCUAAUACAGAACACUUAAUGUAUCAGACAACCAUGAUUAUGAUGUAUAUACCUGGUAUAAACAAUCUUUUUUGCAUAUUGAAUUCUGCAUUUUUUUCUUCCUUGAUACGUAUGAGAUUCACCAGUACCAGUUUUUCUCUUGUGGUGGCAUAUAGUUGAUUGUCAUUUGCAUUAUCUAUUAAAAACCUGUGGCAGCUCAUGGUAUUAUUGACCAUAUGUUCUAGUGUCUUCUUGCAGAUUUAAAUAUUUUAUUGCAGUGUAAAGUUUAAUAUUUAGAUGUGUGAUACAUCUUUGGAUAAUCUGUAAUUAAAUUGAUCUUUUGUAAUGGUGAUAGUGAUUAGCACACACUGAAAAUCCAGCAAAGCAAUUAUUUUUCUCUUUUUAACUGGAAAUCAUAUUCGUAAGUUGUGGUAGAUAUUAUCAUCAGUGUAUUCAUGAUUCGAUUUAUAUUUUGUGUUAUCUGGUUAUAAAUUUUAUAUAGCAUUCAAUUUGACAAAAUAUAAAUCUAUUUGAUUUGAA